GUGGCUCGCUUCGCCGCGCUCCCUCCUUCCCCGCCUUCCAUACCUCCCCGGCUCCGCUCGGUUCCUGGCCACCCCGCAGCCCCUGCCCAGGUGCCAUGGCCGCAUUGUACCGCCCUGGCCUGCGGUGAGUGACCCCCGGCCCGGGGCCCACCCGCACCUUCCGCUGCGCUCGCCCCCUCGGGGCUGCCAGUGGCGCUCUCCUGCUCUCAGCCUCCGCCAGGUUUCCCAUCCUAGGCGGAGGCGGGCAGGGGCGACUGCUGUGGGUCCAGCCUCCCGCGCCGCGCGUCUCUUGGGAGGGCAGCCGGCCGGUGCUCCUCGUUUCCGCCUGCACCUCCCCUUCUCUGCCUCGCUCGCCUCUGACCGCGCGAUCUCUAUCUGCCACUCUCAGAACUUCCUCUCUCUCCUCGCUCCUCUCUGCUGAGCCAGGUCUCCGCAUAUCCUCCUUUCCUUCCCAGAUACCUCCCUCGGACCUCUAACGGGCUCUCAGCCAGCGCCCCAGGGUACUUCGAGAGGCAGCAGGGCCCUGGGGACAAGGGCUUAACUGGCAUGGGCUGAGCCCCUUGGGCUGGCCAUCAUGCCGUAGCAUCCAGACCCUGCGAGUGCUUAGUGGAGAUCUGGGCCAGCUUCCCACUGGCAUUCGAGAUUUUGUAGAGCACAGUGCCCGCCUGUGCCAACCAGAGGGCAUCCACAUCUGUGAUGGAACUGAGGCUGAGAAUACUGCCACACUGACCCUGCUGGAGCAGCAGGGCCUCAUCCGAAAGCUCCCCAAGUACAAUAACUGCUGGCUGGCCCGCACAGACCCCAAGGAUGUGGCACGAGUAGAGAGCAAGACGGUGAUUGUAACUCCUUCUCAGCGGGACACGGUACCACUCCCGCCUGGUGGGGCCCGUGGGCAGCUGGGCAACUGGAUGUCCCCAGCUGAUUUCCAGCGAGCUGUGGAUGAGAGGUUUCCAGGCUGCAUGCAGGGCCGCACCAUGUAUGUGCUUCCAUUCAGCAUGGGUCCUGUGGGCUCCCCGCUGUCCCGCAUCGGGGUGCAGCUCACUGACUCAGCCUAUGUGGUGGCAAGCAUGCGUAUUAUGACCCGACUGGGGACACCUGUGCUUCAGGCCCUGGGAGAUGGUGACUUUGUCAAGUGUCUGCACUCCGUGGGCCAGCCCCUGACAGGACAAGGGGAGCCAGUGAGCCAGUGGCCGUGCAACCCAGAGAAAACCCUGAUUGGCCACGUGCCCGACCAGCGGGAGAUCAUCUCCUUCGGCAGCGGCUAUGGUGGCAACUCCCUGCUGGGCAAGAAGUGCUUUGCCCUACGCAUCGCCUCUCGGCUGGCCCGGGAUGAGGGCUGGCUGGCAGAGCACAUGCUGAUCCUGGGCAUCACCAGCCCUGCAGGGAAGAAGCGCUAUGUGGCAGCCGCCUUCCCUAGUGCCUGUGGCAAGACCAACCUGGCUAUGAUGCGGCCUGCACUGCCAGGCUGGAAAGUGGAGUGUGUGGGGGAUGAUAUUGCUUGGAUGAGGUUUGACAGUGAAGGUCGACUCCGGGCCAUCAACCCUGAGAACGGCUUCUUUGGGGUUGCCCCUGGUACCUCUGCCACCACCAAUCCCAACGCCAUGGCUACAAUCCAGAGUAACACUAUUUUUACCAAUGUGGCUGAGACCAGUGAUGGUGGCGUGUACUGGGAGGGCAUUGACCAGCCUCUUCCACCUGGUGUUACUGUGACCUCCUGGCUGGGCAAACCCUGGAAACCUGGUGACAAGGAGCCCUGUGCACAUCCCAACUCUCGAUUUUGUGCCCCGGCUCGCCAGUGCCCCAUCAUGGACCCAGCCUGGGAGGCCCCAGAGGGUGUCCCCAUUGACGCCAUCAUCUUUGGUGGCCGCAGACCCAAAGGGGUACCCCUGGUAUACGAGGCCUUCAACUGGCGUCAUGGGGUGUUUGUGGGCAGCGCCAUGCGCUCUGAGUCCACUGCUGCAGCAGAACACAAAGGGAAGAUCAUCAUGCACGACCCAUUUGCCAUGCGGCCCUUUUUUGGCUACAACUUCGGGCACUACCUGGAACACUGGCUGAGCAUGGAAGGGCGCAAGGGGGCCCAGCUGCCCCGUAUCUUCCAUGUCAACUGGUUCCGGCGUGACGAGGCAGGGCACUUCCUGUGGCCAGGCUUUGGGGAGAAUGCUCGGGUGCUAGACUGGAUCUGCCGGCGGUUAGAGGGGGAGGACAGUGCCCGAGAGACACCCAUUGGGCUGGUGCCAAAGGAAGGAGCCUUGGAUCUCAGCGGCCUCAGAGCUAUAGACACCACUCAGCUGUUCUCCCUCCCCAAGGACUUCUGGGAACAGGAGGUUCGUGACAUUCGGAGCUACCUGACAGAGCAGGUCAACCAGGAUCUGCCCAAAGAGGUGUUGGCUGAGCUUGAGGCCCUGGAGAGACGUGUGCACAAAAUGUGACCUGAGGCCCUAGUCUAGCAAGAGGACAUAGCACCCUCAUCUGGGAAUAGGGAAGGCACCUUGCAGAAAAUAUGAGCAAUUUGAUAUUAACUAACAUCUUCAAUGUGCCAUAGACCUUCCCACAAAGACUGUCCAAUAAUAAGAGAUGCUUAUCUAUUUUA